GGCGGAAGCGGGAGCCUCUGUCGGCCGCGGAAGCCUGGAGUGGGCGGUACGCAGACGCGCGCGGUGAGACCCGCUGUCUGCUCAGCGGACUCUGCCCGCCCCCACCUCCCCCUGCGUCGGGCCGACAUGAAGGACUCGCUGGUGCUGCUGGGCCGUGUCCCGGCGCACCCGGACUCCCGCUGCUGGUUCCUGGCCUGGAACCCCGCGGGGACCCUGCUGGCCUCGUGCGGCGGCGACCGGAGAAUCCGCAUCUGGGGCACGGAGGGUGACAGCUGGAUCUGCAAGUCUGUCCUUUCUGAAGGCCACCAGCGCACCGUGCGGAAGGUAGCCUGGUCCCCCUGCGGUAAUUACCUGGCCUCUGCCAGCUUUGAUGCUACCACUUGCAUUUGGAAGAAGAACCAGGAUGACUUUGAGUGUGUAACCACUCUCGAGGGCCAUGAAAAUGAGGUCAAGUCAGUGGCUUGGGCCCCAUCUGGCAACCUCCUGGCCACUUGCAGCCGAGAUAAGAGCGUUUGGGUCUGGGAAGUUGAUGAAGAGGAUGAGUAUGAAUGUGUCAGUGUUCUCAACUCCCACACACAGGAUGUCAAGCAUGUGGUUUGGCACCCAAGUCAGGAGCUCUUAGCUUCUGCCAGCUAUGAUGACACAGUGAAGCUGUACCGGGAGGAAGAGGAUGACUGGGUAUGCUGUGCCACCCUUGAGGGCCAUGAAUCCACUGUGUGGAGCUUGGCCUUUGACCCGAGUGGCCAGCGCCUGGCGUCUUGUAGUGAUGACCGUACUGUGCGUAUCUGGCGUCAGUAUCUACCAGGCAAUGAACAAGGGGUGGCAUGCAGCGGCUCUGACCCCAGUUGGAAAUGUAUCUGUACUUUGUCCGGCUUCCACUCAAGGACCAUUUAUGACAUUGCUUGGUGUCAGCUGACAGGGGCUCUGGCCACAGCUUGUGGGGAUGACGCGAUCCGCGUGUUUCAGGAGGAUCCCAACUCGGAUCCACAGCAGCCCACCUUCUCCCUGACAGCCCACUUGCAUCAGGCCCAUUCCCAGGAUGUCAACUGUGUGGCCUGGAACCCCAAGGAGCCAGGGCUACUGGCCUCCUGCAGUGAUGAUGGGGAGGUGGCCUUCUGGAAGUAUCAGCGGCCUGAAGGCCUCUGAGCUACCUCGACUUUGGACAGAGUAAUGACUCCCCAGAAAACGUCAUAUAAGACUUUACCAGCCCCUGAGAGGACCAGGAGGAGCAUCCUUGACCUUCAUUUAACUUGGCUCACUUCUCUUCAGACUUGGGUAGAAGUGCAGAGCCACAGAAUUGCUUUCCUUCCCCGCCUUUGACAUGAGGCCUUCAGUAAAGAGCUACAGAACAUGAGUACAUUGUUAUACCACAGAUUUUUCUUGCAUUAGGGCACAGUGUUAAAUUUUUUGGAGGUAAAUAUACUAUUUAUAAUCACUAUAUAUAGUAGGAGGGGGUAUGUGUCUCAGGCUUUUCUGAAGUUGCAAGACUUAAAGAAAUAAUCCAUCUGCAUCCCAAGUCCUAUUUUAUAAGGAUAUUCAUAAAAAUUCCAUGGUGAAUCCUUGUCUGAAAUAGGUCCUCCCUUCCCAGUUUCUGUGUAAGUCUUUGCAUUUAAGACAUCCAAUCAAUAAUGAAGGAAAUUUUUUUCUGAAUGUAGGUUUGAGUGAGGGGCACCUCUGCUUUCCCUUAGCAACCCUCAUAUACCUCCCUGCACCGUUACGCUGUGAUGGCAACUGGGGAUAGAAAAAAAAUGGGGAAAGACAGGAAUCCUAAAAGGGAGAGUUAUUACUGGCCACAAGCCCUGUAUUCUCAACAGGGAUGCAAAUUGGUUCUUCAGUAAGGAUAAAAAAAAAUCACAAGCAGUUGUUUGUGGCCCUCCUAAGGCCCACAGCACAUAUAGUGUGUCUGUGAUAUUCCAUUUUCAUGGCAGGGAGUGAUCAGGAAGAAGGCUUCCUAGGGGACUGGCGAUUUAAACCAGUUGAGAAACACUGCCAUCAGCAGGCAGUUUCAGACUCACUCAAGUUGUCUCUUGACAGUCACUUCUAAAUGGGUUCUAAUGUGACAAUGGCCUCCAAAACUACAGCCUUCCCUGAAGUUUAAGCUGUGACCUUAGAUUUUAGAAGGACAGUGGGGCUGUACCUAGAAUAGUGGUUCUCGAAGAAUGCGGCCUGCAGAUCCUGGGAGUCCCAAGACCCUUUCAGGGAGGAUCUGUGAGGUCAACUGUUGGCACUGUGGCAUGAAUCAAGGUGGUGGCAGCAAACUUCUAGUAGUUUUGAUAUGUCCUUGAUAGAACAAAUAGCAAUGGUUAACUAUUAAAUGUUGACCUAGCCAGCGCAGUGGCUCAUGCCUGUAAUCCCAGCACUUUGGGAGGCUGAGGCGGGCGGAUCACCUGAGGUCGGGAGUUCGAGGCCAGCCUGACCAACAUGGAGAAACCCCGUCUCUUCUAAAAAUACAAAAUUAGCUGGGCAUGGUGGUGCAUGCCUGUAAUUCCAGCUACUCGGGAGGCUGAGGCAAGAGAAUCGCUUGAAUCCGGUAGGUGGAGGUUGCAGUGAGCCGAGAUCAUACCAUUGCACUCCAGCCCAGGCAACAAGAGUGAAACCCUGUCUCAAAAAGAAAAAAAAAGUUGACCUUGAGAAUUUAUAAUAUUCUGAGAAAACUGGAAGCAUGCAUAAAGCCCCUCUGCUGUGCACUGAAGUAUGGGUGCCUUGAGGAAAAGCAGUUACACAGUUGAGUUGCAAGCUGAAUUGGCUGUGUUCAAGGCAUGCCCUUUAGAAUUGAAAGAACUAGCAGAUUACGGUAUUUAGACUUGAAUAUUUGGCUGAUAUUUUCUGGAAAUUAAUGGAAUGAGCCUCUCACCUCAAGGGAAACAACUGAUAGUGUUGCCAGUGAUAAAGCUUUCAAGCAAAAAUUGGAAUUUCCGAAAAUCUGUACUCCACCAUGAGCUUUAUUGUUGGGGAUAUUAACAAAUGUGAUUUGUAUAAUGAAAUGCAUUUCAUUUGGAAGAAUUCAAUGAACCAUUUUUCCAAGUGACCAGUACGUGAUGUUACAAAAUCAUGCAUGGCUCAAAGAUUGAUUCAAAAGUGUAAGACAGGCCAGUGGAUUUUAAUGUAUUAACAAUAUAAGAGUGCAUUAAGUUUUCGGAGUCUACAUUGCCUUUAAGAAACUAUGACUUGUAGUAAGCCGGGCGCGGUGGCUCACGCCUGUAAUCCCAACACUUUGGGAGGCCAAGGUGGGUGGAUCACAAGGUCAGGAGUUCAAGACCAGCCUGGCCAAUAUGGUGAAAGUCCGUCUCUACUAAAAUUACAAAAAUUAGCCGGGCGUGGUGGCAGAUCCCUUGUAGUCCCAGCUACUCGGGAGGCUGAGGCAGGAGAAUAGCUUGAACCCGGGAGGUGGAGGUUGCAGUGAGUCGAGAUCGUGCCACUGGACUCCAGCCUGGGUGACAGAGCGAGACUCCAUUUCAAAAAAAAAAAAAAAAAAAAAAAAUCACUUGUAGUCUUGGUGUGGUAUCAAAGAAUAGCCACAAUUAGCUGAAAAGGCUAUUUUAAAAACUUUUCCAACUGCGUAUCUGUGUGAAGUCAACUUACUUCAACAAAAAAGUUUGGAUGUAGAAGCAGCUGUAAGAAUUCAACUGUUUAUUAUAACAAGAUACUAAAGAGACUGUAAAAUGCCACCCUUCUCCUUGGAUUGUUUUGGAAGUUAUUCUUCAUAAAAAAUGUUAACGUGGGCUGGGCAUGGUGGCUCAUGCCUGUAAUCCCAGCACUCUGGGAGGCUGAGGUGGGCGGAUCACUUGAGCUCAGGAAUUCAAGGUCAGCCUGGGCAACAUGGCUAAACUCUGUCUCUAUUAAGAAAAAAAAUGUUAACAUUAUGAUUUAAAAGUGCAUUAACCUUAAUCUAGAUAAUAAAAGCUUUUUGGGGCAACCUCCAGAACUGUGAAAAAUAAAUUUGUUAUUUAAAAAGAAAAAAAAAAAAA